CUCUUUUGGGGUUCUUCCUUUCUCUCUCAGCUCUCCGUCUCUCUUUCUCUCUCAGCCUCUUUCUUUCUCCCUGUCUCCCCCACUGUCAGCACCUCUUCUGUGUGGUGAGUGGACCGCUUACCCCACUAGGUGAAGAUGUCAGCCCAGGAGAGCUGCCUCAGCCUCAUCAAGUACUUCCUCUUCGUUUUCAACCUCUUCUUCUUCGUCCUCGGCAGCCUGAUCUUCUGCUUCGGCAUCUGGAUCCUCAUUGACAAGACCAGCUUCGUGUCCUUUGUGGGCUUGGCCUUCGUGCCUCUGCAGAUCUGGUCCAAAGUCCUGGCCAUCUCAGGAAUCUUCACCAUGGGCAUCGCCCUCCUGGGUUGUGUGGGGGCCCUCAAGGAGCUCCGCUGCCUCCUGGGCCUGUAUUUUGGGAUGCUGCUGCUCCUGUUUGCCACACAGAUCACCCUGGGAAUCCUCAUCUCCACUCAGCGGGCCCAGCUGGAGCGAAGCUUGCGGGACGUCGUAGAGAAAACCAUCCAAAAGUACGGCACCAACCCCGAGGAGACCGCGGCCGAGGAGAGCUGGGACUAUGUGCAGUUCCAGCUGCGCUGCUGCGGCUGGCACUACCCGCAGGACUGGUUCCAAGUCCUCAUCCUGAGAGGUAACGGGUCGGAGGCGCACCGCGUGCCCUGCUCCUGCUACAACUUGUCGGCGACCAACGACUCCACAAUCCUAGAUAAGGUGAUCUUGCCCCAGCUCAGCAGGCUUGGACACCUGGCGCGGUCCAGACACAGUGCAGACAUCUGCGCUGUCCCUGCAGAGAGCCACAUCUACCGCGAGGGCUGCGCGCAGGGCCUCCAGAAGUGGCUGCACAACAACCUUAUUUCCAUAGUGGGCAUUUGCCUGGGCGUCGGCCUACUCGAGAUGACUGUCAUGGUGCUGAGCGUACAGCUACAGCGCAGGGCACUCCGCCGGAAAUGCGAGCCGCACGUGCCGGGCGCUGGGGAUUCGAGCCCCGGGCCCAGCCUGAUCGCUGACGGCGGCGGCGGGCACAGCGGCAGUCUGUGGGGUGGCUGGGGCAUGGCGGGUGCCUGCCCCAACUGGGGAGACAAGGCACCGCAGGGCAAGCUGCCCAUGGCCCUGGGGCUCUGGCCGCUGUGGGUUCAAGACGAGGACCAGCCUGACACUGGAAGUGCGGGCGCAGAAUUAGAGGAGGCACAAUUAGAGGCUGAGGCAGAGGGGGAAGACAGAUGAGCCUCCAAAAUAAAGGACCCUGGGCUUGCUUCCGACCUUACUCCUUCUCAGCCUCUACCCCCACUUGUAGCAGCUAUUCCCGCCUCAUCAGCCAGCCCUGCGGCAGUUCCCGUCGAGCCCCGCCCUUUUCUACCUAUCCCCUUCUCCAGCCCCUUCCCGCCCAAUUCACGGCCCCACCCCUGACCUUUCUCGCCCGGGUGGGCAUCACCCCCGUCUCGCCAGCACCCCUUCGACUUCUCUGACCUCAUCUCCUUUCUCUAUAGCUCGGGUUCAUGACGCUCUCGAUAUUCCUGUGCAGAAACCUGGACCACGUCUACAACCGGCUCGCUCGAUACCGUUAGGCCCCGCCCUCCCCAAAGUCCCGCCCCGCCCCCGUCACGUGCGCUGGGCACUUCCCUGCUGCCUGUAAAUAUUUGUUUAAUCCCCAGUUCGCCUGGAGCCCUCCGCCUUCACAUUCCCCUGGGGACCCACGUGGCUGCGUGCCCCUGCUGCUGUCACCUCUCCCACGGGACCUGGGGCUUUCGUCCACAGCUUCCUGUCCCCAUCUGUCGGCCUACCACCACCCACAAGAUUAUUUUUCACCCAAACCUCAAAUAAAUCCCCUGCGUUUUUGGUAAAA